GACAUCGCCAAACCUCGCCCAGAUUCAGGCGUGUAAACCAGCCGGAGCGGCGCGGCAGCGGCAGGACCGCCGUGGCGCCUAGAGUAGCGACCCGGGGGGAGCGCGGGGCGACGCUGGCUGCAGGGACCCGGUGACAGCGUGAGAGGUUCGCAGAGUACUAGGUUUUGACAAGCUUGCAUCAUGCGUGAGUAUAAGCUAGUCGUUCUUGGCUCAGGAGGCGUUGGAAAGUCUGCUUUGACUGUACAAUUUGUUCAAGGAAUUUUUGUAGAAAAAUACGAUCCUACGAUAGAAGAUUCUUAUAGAAAGCAAGUUGAAGUAGAUGCACAACAGUGUAUGCUUGAAAUCUUGGAUACUGCAGGAACGGAGCAAUUUACAGCAAUGAGGGAUUUAUACAUGAAAAAUGGACAAGGAUUUGCAUUAGUUUAUUCCAUCACAGCACAGUCCACAUUUAACGAUUUACAAGACCUGAGAGAACAGAUUCUUCGAGUUAAAGACACUGAUGAUGUUCCAAUGAUUCUUGUUGGUAAUAAGUGUGACUUGGAAGAUGAAAGAGUUGUAGGGAAGGAACAAGGUCAAAAUCUAGCAAGACAAUGGAACAACUGUGCAUUCUUAGAAUCUUCUGCAAAAUCAAAAAUAAAUGUUAAUGAGAUCUUUUAUGACCUAGUGCGGCAAAUUAACAGAAAAACUCCAGUGCCUGGGAAGGCUCGCAAAAAGUCAUCAUGUCAGCUGCUUUAAUAUACUAAAUGCAUUGUAGCUCUGAGCCAGGUCUGAAGAACUGUUGCCCAAUUCAACAGUGCCAGCAUUCCAACUUUGUUAAACCUACCAACAUCUUAAAUGGACUUUCCUGUGGUGGUACCCUUUAAGAGGCGGAUGAAAGCUACUAUAUCAGUUUGCACAUUCUAAUCACUUUCCAGUAUCACAAGAGAGAUUUUUACUUAUAUAAUAGUCCUAGAGUUUGCAGCUGGUAAAACCAGAGGCUACAUCCAGUAUUACUGCUAAGAGACAUUCUUCAUCCACCAAUGUUGUACAUGUAUGAAAAUGGUGUACUGUAUACUUUAACAUGCCCCAUACUUUGUAUUGGAGAGUACAAUAAUGUAAAUCCUAAAAGCACCACUAUUUUAGCAUAAUAAAAGAAAGUCCAAAGAGCUCCUAUAUAGACUACUCCAGAUAACUUCGCUUCUUUGAUACUUGUAGCUUAUUGUAAUUUUUUUUAAGAAAUUCAAGGUCAUUAUUAUUGUACAAAAUAAGCGCUUUGAUUAACACAGCUAUAUAGUUUUUUUAAUUUUUAAAAAACCUGUGGAGACGGUGAUCUUGUCUUUAAAACAUGAUAGUCCUUUCAGUAUAAUGUCUUAGAUUAAAGACGUUGCCUUUAAUAUCUGUUGGGAAGGAAAUGUCCAGACUUUUCAAAUCUCUUAUUAUAUGUUUCCUUUUUUUGUUUACAUAGGGAACAAUGUUUAUAGUCGUGUGUACAGUGGGGGUCUACAACAAGAAGUGUAUAUUUUCAAACAAUUUUUUAAUGAUUUAACAAUUUUUGUAAAUCAUUUUCAGGCUUCUGCAGCUGUAGAUUCUCACUGUGAAUCCCUUGCUUGCUCAUGCAUAAGUGUAUUUGCAAUACCAAAUAUACAGGUUUAGUAUUUUUGCCUGUUAGUGAUUGUUUCACAUGUGUAACGUUUUGGUUGAGAUGUUAAAUGGUGGACGAGUACUGUGGAUGUGAAUGUGGGAAGUAAUUUUAAUCAUAUGUAAUUGGUCACAAGGCCUAAUUUGCAGUAACUAUUGCUGUUUUAUUUAACAAUGCCUUGUUGCUUUGUAUGCAUUAAUGUUUGGAUGUAAAGAUUGUGUGUCUAUCCAACAGGGAGCCACAGUAUUUAAAUUGACCAACCUAAUGUUACAACUACUUUGAGGUGGCCAAAUGUAAACUAAAAGCCUUAAUUAAAGUGGUGCAAUUUUGUAUAACUUAGCAUCAGUAGUUCAAUAAAUUUGGAUUGCCAUGCAAGGGCUUGCAUUAUAAUUACUUGCCACUUGAAUGUGUUUUGUGUAAUGUUUUAACAGUGCUAGUAAAUAAAUACGGGUUUACCCUGGUUUUAAUUGUAAUAGGUGCAUUUUACACAGCAUGGUUUCAUAAUUUAACAUCUGGGCAAGCCAGACUCAUUAAUUACAGGAAUAAGGAAGUAGCGAGUUUUCUGGUAUUGUUUGAAUAUCCACAUAACCACCUUUUGAACUUUUCCUUGAGAAAUAAUUUUGUAAAUCAAGCAGUAUUACUUACGAAUAAAUGCCUUUGGGUAAUGUUCAGUAGCUAUUUGAUGAGGUAGGUAAAAGAGGAACGAUUUAACAUACUUUCAUGGAUGUUACACUAUGGAUUUUUUAAAAUACAGGAUUGAAGUUAGAAUAUUGUGGUUAUAAAAAUCUUUGAGUGAUGUGGAUUAAGCACUUAGAGAAUCGAUAUUUUUCUUAAAUAUGCUAUAAUUGAAUUCUGUAAGAACUGAAUUCUUAUAGAAUUAUUUUAAAACUUUUUAAAAAUUGUAAAGCUCUUAAAAAACUUUUUGAAAGUAUUUGCCAGCUACUGGAGCAAUUAAUCAGUGAUAAUAUCUAAUAGAGGGGUAUCUGCUAAUCCCCUAAAUACACGCUGUUUGAAUGAUACAUUUUUAAAGGCUUUCAUGUUAAGAAAAAGUCUGAUUCUUUACAAAAGGGACUUGUUUUGGCAGAACUGGUUUUAUUUAUAAUCAUUUGGGAAAAAAAUUAAGCCCAAAAAACUGGGACUGUGAAACACUAAAAUUACUUCAAUUUACUAUGUCCUGUUACAUCCAUUGAUACCGCCAUUAUUCAAUAAUUACUUUUAAUAAAUGUUUGCUGCCUACCAGCUAUGUACCAGGCCCAGUUCUAGGCUCAAACAGCUAAAUAUUCAUUCAUUGGACAAAUUAAGUACUUAAGUAUAAAAAUUGUUCUAGGCCUAAGGAUGUAGCAGCAACCAAGAUCAACUAUAAAAUGCUGCCCUCCUAGAAUUUAUAUUCUAUUGAAGAGUUUCUCAGCCUCAGCACUAUUGAUGUUUUAUGUUUGAUAAUGUAUUCUGGCGACUCUCCUGUGCAUUAUAGGAAUUUUAAUAUCUGCCCACUAGAUGCCAGUCACACCACCCCAGCCCCCAAGUUGUGGCAACCAAAAAUGUUUCCAGACAUUGCCAGAUGUUCCCCAGUUGGAUUGUUGGGGGACAAGGGAGGUGAACUUGGAGGGCAAAAUCACCCUGGUGAAGAACUACUGCUCUGGUGGGAAACAACACAUUAGUUACAGAUGAGUGUUAGGGUUACAAGAUGGAUGGUUUACUAUAUAGUGAAUAAGAAUAUAAAGUUUGGAGCCAGACUUCCUGGGUUUUUAAUCCCAGCUCUUCCAGUUCCUACUAUAUGCCUUUGGUUGGGUGCCUUGGUUUCCUCAUCUGUAAAAUGAGAAUGAUAAUACCUACUUCAUAGGAGAGUGAAAUGAAUGCCAGUGCUAUCCUCUAGGUCUAUAUAUAUAUAUAUAUAUAUAUAUUAUAUAUAGUACAUAUAUAGAGAGAGUAUAUAUAUAUAUGUAGUACAGUGGAGGUCUAUAUAAUACUAUAUAUAUAAUUUAUUUUUUUCAAUGCUGAUAGGAAUAAGGCUGUGGUUUGGCAAAAAGCACCAUUUUCUCCUAUACAAAAUAGUAACUGCAGUUUGGGAGCACAACUCAUGUAGAUUGACUUUUCUGGUGCUUAAUGGGAAAAUACUAAAAUAAUUGAGUCAGAAAAGGCAUGAAUUCCUUUUCACGUCCCCAAGGAUACUUGAAGAAACUUGAGUUUUAGGAGAAAAUCAGAGUGGUCUUUCACUUACAUUUUUCUAAAAAGUGUAAAAACCCUGUAUUGACUUUCUUGUUGAUUCAGUUGUUUCUUAAACGUAAAUAGCUCAUCUUUACCAUAUGUGGGCAUUACAAAUAGAAAUUUUUAAAAUUCCAUUUAUAAAAUGAAGUUUUGCCGUUUUUUUUUUUAAAUCAUUCCGUCUUUAGUUGUGGGACAGCAAACUUAGAAUCGAAACUCAUCACUACAACUUUUCUUUGAGUUAAACUCUUAUCUGUGUUUUCAUUGAAUUUAAUCUCCAUCUAUUCUAUCUCUUCUUAAAUCUUGGAAAUGUAAAAGGGAGUUAUAGUGUUUUACAAUUAAUACUCUUACUAUUACCUUAGAAGCCUUAAAAGUGCUUGCAGGCUUGUCUCAUAAUCUGUCAGUGAGCCUUAACAUUGUGAUUUGUAAGACUAAAAUUUUUUUUUCAAACAAAACAAAUCUGACAGCCUGGGCAACAUAGACCCCAUCUCUACAAAAAAAAAUUUUUUUUUAAUUAGCUGGGCAUGGUGGUGCACGUCUGUACCUGUAGUCCCAGCUAUUCAGAAGGAUUGCUUGAUCCCAGGAGAUCAAGGAUACAGUGAACUGUGUUCGCGCCACUGCACCCCCACGAUGGCAAUAGAGUGAGACCCUGUCUUAGAAAAAAAAGAUAAAUAAGUCUGUUCUAUUUGUUACAGUGCAUCAACACAUUUGAAUUUUCUUUUUUUUUCUUUUUCUUUUUUUUUUUUGAGACUGAGUUUCGCUCUUGUUGCCCAGGCUGGCGUACAGUGGUGCGAUCUUGGCUCACCCCAACCUCUGCCUCCCAGGUUCAAGCAAUUCUUCUGCCUCAGCCUCCUGAAUAGCUGGGAUUACAAGCAUGCACCACCACGCCUGGCUAAUUUUGUAUUUUUUGGUAGAGAUGAGGUUUCUCCAUGUUGGUUAGGCUGGUUUCGAACUCCCGACCCAGGUGAUCCGCCUGCGUCAGCCUCCCAAAGUGCUGGGAUUACAGGUGUGAGCCACCGCACCCAGCCUAAUCAAUACAUUUGAUAUUUCAAGAAUACAUGAGAGAAGAGAGGUAGAUUGAGAACAGAACUAAACUUUAUAUAUGUUUCCUUAACUAUUGGGAGGAAAAUGGAUGAGUCUGUGUUGGGAUACCUGUUGAAACAAGACUACUAAACAGAUUAAUCAACUAAUUCCAUAGGCUUGACAUUAGUUUAUCUUUGAAAAGUAAAAGUAAAGUGCUUAUUGCUAAAUAGGUCUGUAUUCUAAAUGCUGCCAUUUUUUAAAAAAAGUAUUCCAUGUUACACACAUUUUAAACUUGCUUCUUAAAACAUCCCUGUUGGUGGCCUGUAGGUUACUGACCUUAGGAAUUACAGGCUUUAUCCAAAAUUAGGCAUAUCUACCUGAUUUUUGUAUCUGAGAAUCAAUAAAUGCAUUCAGUAUUCUCUACCGUGUUUCAGGCGCUGUUUACAAUAUCGGAGGUACAGCAGGGAUUUUCUGCCCACGUGGGGAAAACACACAGCAAAUGAACAAAGCUCUAUUGGUAACAGUCUGUUAAACUUUCUAAGAGCUUUCCAACUUUCUAAGAGAAAAUUGUAAUGAUUUUAGAAAAGUGAGCUGUCAUUUUUCAUAUAUAUAAAUUUUUUUAUUCAUAGGUAAUCUAAUUUUUCUCAUUUCUCCAAAAGGGUACGAAGACAGUUUUUACUAUGUUGUUUUACUAUGAACCUAGUUUAACCUGACUUUCCUUACAGACCCACAUAAAUGAGACAAUCCAAAUUUAGUAUUUGGGUCAAAAUGCAGGGUUUUUUCCUGAAAACAAAACAGCACACACAUAUAUUACAGGAUUUUUAUGUAAUAAUAUAUUCACUUCAGUCAGGUUUCAGUUUUUAAAUAGGCAGAGAUCAAAAGCCUCUAAUGUUUUUGUCAUCCGCCAUUAUUACCCAUUCAAAUUUCUAUUUAUGUCUGGUAGUUAUGUCCCCUGUGAGCACUAAUUUCAGAACAGGAAAUUCUAUUAACUGUCAAACUCUUUAAUGUGCAGUGCAGUAGGUUUGGAGCAGAGGGGAGUAGGAAGGAGUAAAUGAUAUAAUCCAGUCUGGCCUGGCAUGGUGGCUCACACUUGUAAUCCCAAUGCUUUGGGAGGCCGAGAUGGGUGGAUCACUGGAAGCCAGGAGUUUGAGACAAGCCUGGCCAACAUGGUGAAACCCCGUCUCUACUAAAAAUAACAAAAAUUAGACGGGCACGGUGGUGUGUGCCUGUAAUCCCAGCUACUCAGGAGGCUGAGGCAGGAGAAUCACUUGAACCUGGGAGGCCGAGGUUGCAGUGAGCUGAGAUCACACCACUGCACUUCAGCAUGGGCAACAGAGUGAGACUGCAAAAAAAAGAAAAAGAAAAAAAAAUCCAGUCUCUGCUGGCAAGGUGUUUAACAAGUCAAUGAUGGGAAAGACCAGUCAAAUAAACUAUCAGAUCUAAUAACUUUUCUAACCAUAGGUGAUUCUUCUUCCAUUAUCCAUACUAAAGCAAGUGACUCAUAAUAAAAAUUGUUAUUUUGUAAAAUAUAUGGACUGUUUGCUUUAUAUUCCCAACUAUUACAUCUGGUUGACUAUUAACAGGUCAAUGUCAGAUUUCCUGAGCAAAUCAACCAAUAAUGAAAAACUAUGUGGCUGGCAGAAAAAAAUAAGUGCGUGUGGUGGUGCUUGCCUGUAAUCCCAGCUGCUUGGGAGGCUGAGGUAGGAGGAACUCUUGAGCUCCGGUGGUUUGAGGCCAGCAUGGAUAACAUAGGGAGACCCUGUCACUUGACAAAAGUAUCUUUCCCUACUGGAAAUGGAAUAGAAUCGGAUGGGUAUGGUACAGCAGGUAGUUAUGGGGAGACCUCUACUGUUCUAAAUGAGACUAAUAGUAAAUGUUACAUAACUAAAGCAACAGAUUUGCCAGCUGUGUGAAAGAUAACCCAGAGAGGGGUAAUGGUAGAGCCAGAAUUAACACAGCCAGCUUGUCAGCUACCUUUGAACAUGUAUUUUCUGUGCAGUCAGAUUUGAAGGGUUGGACCUUGGAGUUACUGACAUUGGAGGCAACUGAAACCAUGAGUGUGAAUGAAAUUAUUUUCGUAAGAAUUACUUGGGGUUAAAAAUAGUAAUAAAAAGGAAAGCCUGGCCUAAACAGUCUUGGGAUGGGGAGAAGGGUUGGAGUACAAAGGAUUGCUAUUACAAAGACAUGGGCAGAGAACAAGGCAAAUAGCUGAGCAGCAAUUGAGAAUACAGCAUCUUUUAUGGCAAAGAGCAAAAUACUAUUGUUCCUCUUCUAGUAUGCUAUAGACCAGCAGUAAUUUUGUGCUCUAAAAUGCUUAUUUUUAUCUCUCUGUAUAUACUUGGUGGUGAAUUUGCUACAAAUGUAAGGAGAUGAUGGGAUAGUUUUUGGAAAUACCAUCCUCUAAUUAGUACCAGGUCUAUGUAUAUCUGCAGCAACUAUAAAGUCUGUUUCAGAGUCAGUAUUGGCAAACUUAUAUUUAAAUUCAGCUGUAACAAGACAUCUUUUUUUUUUUUUUUGAGAGAGUCUGGCUCUGUCACCCAGGCUGGUGUGCAGUGGCGCGAUCUCGGCUCACUGCAACCUCCGCCUCCCAGGUUCAAGCAGUUCUCUGCCUCAGCCUCCCGAGCAGCUGGGAUUACAGGCAUCUGCCACCAAGCCCUGCUAAUUUUUCUAUUUUUAGUAGAGACGGGGUUUCGCCAUCUUGGCCAGGCUGGUCUUGAACUCCUGACCUCGUGAUCCAUCUGCUUCAGCCUCCCAAAGUGCUGGGAUUACUGGCAUGAGCCACUGCGCCCGGCAAGUUGUCUUUCAAAUAUAUGCCUUUGCAGUAUUUCUCUACUUCCCCAGUAAUGUAAACUUUAUUUUCUCUCAAUUUUCGUAAGUGGUAUUUUGGUGCUUUACCCAAAAUAUUAGGGAGAAAAUUCUUCUUUUUAAUUGGAUUCUCGUAUGUUGAUCUAUUUCUAUUGUUUUCUAAAAAAAAGUUAGUGUCCUAGUUUAAAAGUAUAUAUUAGUUUCCUAGGGCUGCUGUAACAAAUUAUCACAAAUUUGGUGGCUUAAAGCAACAGAAAUGUACUCUUUCACAGUUCUGAAGGUCGAAGUCCAAAAUCAAAGUGUUAGGAUGUACUCCUAGAGGCUCUCGGAGAGAACCUGUUCCCAUGGCAUUAUGCCACAUCACAUGUGCCUCUAUCUUUGUAUCUCCUCCUCUCUAUAAUCUUUCUUUUAAAAGGACAAUUGUUUUGACAUUUAGGGCUUACCCACAUACUUCAGGAUAAUCUCAUCUCAAAAUGCUUAAUCACAUCUGCAAAGACACUUUUUUCAAAUAAAGUUAACAGACAGAAGUUUGGGGGUUGGGAUGUGGACAUGCCUUUGGGAGCCAUUAACAACCUACCAAAACAUUUUAACAAUUUUUCAGUACCAAAGACUAGUAUGGGUCUGCUCCAAGAUAACUCAAAACAUUCUGAACUGAAUCAGCAGACCCUCAGGUCUCCCUAGAGAGAUCCUGAGCACCUAGGAAAGCCCCAGAAUUAAGCUACUCUACAAGGAUUCUGAGGGAAGUCUGGGAUUAGGUGAGACUUUAAUGAGUCCAUCAGAGGUUUAGUAUGGACUAGUUCUACAGUUCCAGAAGCAACAUACUGGGUAUGGAAUAUUGUUAACCAUUGUCAUCCCACAGAAUUACCUUCUACUUGUGUCAGUAUAUAUCCUGCCUACCCUACAUAUUUUAUAUUUAUCAAUGAUGACAGAAACUUCCCCCCUUUUACUUAGAUCUAAUAGUAAUAUAACAAACUUUUCUUUUUCAUUUUCAGACAUAUCCAGAGGGUUUUCUCUUCAUCUCACGCAUCCCACCUUUAAUCAGACAUAUGUGAUUCAUAUGAGAGAAAAUUAGUGUUUCUGAGACCAAAUGGUGGUGUUUAUAAGAUUUUGCUUCUGCACUGAAUUCAAUGUUUUAUUUACUGCUUGGUUAUUUUGUUUUUGUUUUUUAAGAAAUGGGAGGAGUGUAAUAUCUAGAGGUACAUGAAAAAAAGAAAUGGAAGGAAUGGACAGGCCCAGAAUUAAAUGAUAAAAACUCAUCUGGUUGGAAUGAAGUACACUGAACAUUUGAGGAAGUUAGAGAUUAAUUCAACCCAGUGGGUUUUGGGGUUUUUAUAUGUGUUAGUACAUUCAGCGUUAGGGUUGGGUUUCUUGUCUCUGUAAUCACUUCUCAAAAAUGAAUUUGGGCUUCUCCAGAUAGCCUUUUUAUCCAUUUAUUAUUUCAAGUAAUGGUAUAAGGAAAUUGUAACCAUUUGUGUGCUUUACAUGUUUAAGAUACAAACUUACAGUUCCCAGAAGUCAAUUCAGUCAUUCUCUAUAAGAGCUGUUGUGGAAAAAGUUCUCACUUCACUUACUCAUUCCUUUGCAUUUUCCAACUUUAGUAAAGCAUGACUUCAUGCCUUGGAUCAUACAGGAUUUCAACGGGAGAUUUAUAAGUCUAUUUUGUUAGAAUAAAAAGCAAUAAUACUUCCUGAAAUACAUCUUGGGCUCUUUGCAGAAGCUGAACUAUCUGGUAAUUACUAUUUAGCAAACAGCUAACAGCUAGCUCUUAAUUUUUCAGAAAUAAGAGGACAUCAUUGGCCACUAUCAUACCACUAAUUUUAUUCCACCAAUGCUUUCACAGAGGAUGUCACCAAAGAAAGAAGUGGCAUCCACUACCCCUCCCCCAUCCUUCCACUCUGAACCAGUACAGGAUAUUCUCAUGGUCAGGGCAUUCUCUCCUUGGCAGGAUGUAGUUAAUGACAUAUGCAGAAUUAAUGACUUGGUUGCCCUAGGCCCCCCGUCAAGGCUUUUGUUCAAGGGAGAGUAAAGAGGAUAGGUCUCAGUAUGUCAUCCAAACAGGAUGGAUACAGAAUGCCAACCAGGUUAGCCCUGGCAAGUUAAGACAUUUUACAGUGCCACUACCUACCUCCAUACUGUAUCAGAGGAGCCAGUUGCACAGUGUUGAUCUCCCUAAGACUAUUAUAAUAAGGAAGGGGUUUUUUUCUUAGCCCAGUUACUACUAAAACUCACUCAGAGGAGCAAGUGAAAUUUGUCACAAUUGGCUCGACUGCUUUAUCUCACUUUGAAAAAGAAAAGUUACAAAUUCUAGUAAGCAAAAGAUUUUUUGUGACCAGGUCUCCCUGACCUGCACAAAAUAAACUCUUCAUGAGUUAAACCAAAACAGAUUUAAUGUCUAAACUUAAAUCUAGUUUGACAUUAACUUCUUUUCCAAAGAGAAAUAACGUUAACAAUCUGAAAUCAUCCCUGCACAGACUUUCUUGGCUCUUCUUUUCUGCCGUCCUAUGAAUCACAAAUAGAAGUUUAAGAAAGCUGUCAGGUAGGCGCCUCAAAUUCAUUUAAAAUGAGGAAUGAUGAAAGAAUAAGAAAAACCAGCAAAUGAUAGCUUACUUAUUCAGUUAUUUGGCUUGAUACUGCUUGAAAGUGACAUUUCUAGAUUAAAGAUCUGAUAAGCUCUGAUAGUUGGGAAAUAAUACUAGUUAUUUCUUGGACACCCUAAGAUGUGCCACCAUUGCUCUAAGCACUUUACAUGUGUUGUUCAACCCUCAGCAAUGCUAUGAAAUAGGGGCUGAGUCUCCUAAUAGAGCUAAUGAAUGCAUUAUAUCAAAAGAAUGAAAUGUUAAAUAUAGACACUGGAAAAUAAAAUUACUUUUGCUUGUAUUAUAAGUGAAUACCUUGAAAGCUCAAAAAAAUCUAUUAGAAGUAUUCAGGAACUUGGCUGGAUAUAAGAUAAGCAUGCCAAAAAUCAAUAGCUUUUCUUUAUAUUUAUAAAAAAUACCUACAAGUUGAUAUAGUAAACACGACAGAUAAAAACUAAAUGCCUUAAGGUAUAAGGCUAAGAAAGAACUAUUAUAAACUCUUAUUGAAGGACAUAAAUCAAGAUCUGAACAAAUACACUGGGAAGAUAAUAUCAUAAAAAUAUCAAUUCCCCCAAAUUAGCAUGUUAAUGUAUAAUGAUUACAAUUUAAAUUUCAACUGGCUGAGGCUUUGUUUUUGUUUUUGAUUUUUUAAUAGACUGGAUGUUGGUCUUGAACUCCUGGGCUCAAGCAAGUGUCACACCUUGGCCUCCCAAAGUGGAUUAUAGGCAUGAGCCACCGUGCCAGACUUGGGUGAGGUUUUGAAAUUGAAAUUAAGCAAAAUGGGCCGGGCACGGUGGCUCACACCUGUAAUCCCAGCACUUUCGGAGGCCGAGGGGGGCGGAUCACGAGGUCAGGAGAUGGAGACCAUCCUGGCUAACAUGGUGAAACCCCGUCUCUACUAAAAAUACAAAAAUUAGCCAGGCAUGGUGGCAGGUGCCUGUAAUCCCAGCUACUCUGGAGGCUGAGGCAGGAGAAUCGCUUGAACCCAGGAGGCAGAGGGUGCAGUAGCUGAGAUUGUACCACUGCACUCCAGCCUGGGUGACAGAGCAAAUCUCUAUCUCAAGAAAAAGAAAAAAGAAAAGAAAUUAAGCAAAAUGAUCUUAAAGUUCAAGUGAAAGAGUAGAGUAGAACUGAGUCCAGAACUAGAUUCCAGUAUAUGACGUUUAUACGUGACAAAAAUAUAUUUCUUUUUCUUUCUUUUUUUUUUUUUUUUUUUUGAGACAGUUUCCCUCUUGUUGCCCAGACUGGAGUAUAAUGGCACGAUCUUGGUUCACCACAACCUCCGCCUCCCAGGUUCAAGUGAUUCUCCUGCCUCAGCCUCCCGAGUAGCUGGGAUUACAGGCAUGUGCCACCACGCCUGGGCUAAUUUUGUAUUUUAGUAGAGAUGGGGUUUCUCCAUGUUGGUCAGGCUAGUUGCGAACUCCCAACCUCAGGUCAUCUGCCCGCCUCAGCCUCCCAAAGUACUGGGAUUACAGGUGUGAGCCACUGUGCCCGGCCGACAAAAAUAUAUUUCAAUAGAAAAUAGUAUCAGUAAAAUGCUAGCACAACUAACUAUCUGUCUAAAGACAAUAAAAGUUCAACCCCUAUAUCAUGCAAAAAGCACUUUCCAGAUAUAUUAAAAUGUUUUCAAGCUAUAAAGUAAAACAGUAGAAGUCUUAGAAGAAAAUCUAAGAGACUAGAAAUCUAGAGAUAGGGUAGACCUUCUUAGCUAAUUUUUAAAAAUGAAGCUAUAUUUAAGAUAUAUAUUUCAAGUAAAUAAUAAGUGUGUGUGUGUGUACACACAGAUGCUUCUCAGCUUACAAUGGGGUUAUGUCCCAAUAAGCCCAUCAGAAGUCAAAAAUGUAAGUCGAAAAUGCAUUUAAUACCCUGAUAAAUCCAUCACAAAGCUGAAAAAUUAUAAGUAAAACUGUAAGUCACAGACUGUAUAUAUAAAUUUAAAAUUUGGCAAAAUAUAUUGCAAAGUCAAAUUUGGGAAAGUAUAGCACAGAUAAAAGAUUAAACUAUUCACGGCCAGGCACGGUGGAUCAUGCCUGUAAUCCCAACACUUUGGGAGGCCGAGGCGGGUGGAUCACCUGAGGUCAGGAGUUUGAGACUAGCCUGGCCAACGUGGAGAAACCCCAUCUCUACUAAAAAUACAAAAUUAGCUGGGUGUGGUGGUGCAUGCCUGUAAUCCUAGCUACUCAGGAGGCUGAGGCAGGAGAAUUGCUUGAACCUAGGAGGCGAAAGUUGCAGUGAGCCAAGAUGGUGCCAUUGCACUCCAGCCUGGGCAACAAGAGUGAUACUCCGUUUAAAAAAAAAAAAAAAAAAAAAGGUAAACUAUUCAAAAGAUAAAUGGUUGAAAGAUAUAUAACUAGGCAGUUUAGAUAAGAACAAAUCCAAAUGGCCCAUCAACAUAAAAAGAUGCUCUAACUGUAGCCAGAGAAAUACGAAUCAAAGUACCAACGAGCCCAACACAUGGACGAAAACUUCAGAGAACACUACAGUCCCAGAAGAGAGGUAAAGGGCAAGAAAUGAAUCAUUUAUUGCUGAUGGAAAUGUGCAUUGUAGAGCUGAUAUCUGUUCAAAUUAAAUAUGCAUAUUUGACCUCAAUUCUACUACUGAUAUCUACACCAAGGAAAUGAAAGGAAAUGCACAAGAUUAUUUAUUGCCACACUCUAGAAGGAAAAACAGAGUGCAUGCCCAUCAAUAGAAUAGUUGAAUAAAUUAUGAUUCAUGCAUAAUAUAGAACAUUAUGCAUUCAUUUAAAAAUGAGUUUGAUGUUUAAAGGUUGACUUAGAAGGAUUCCCGUGCAAAGUGAACAAAACAGAAUACCGAGAAGGAUGUAUGUGAGGGAUGCAUGUGGGCACCUGGGAAAGGAGAUGAAGAAAGCAACUGAAGGAUAUUUACCAAGUUGUUAAUAUGCAUUACCUGACAUGGUGAUAUAGGAGUAGGGGUGAGGAAGUGAAGGAUCUGAGUAGGUGGAAAAAGAAAAGCAAAAGUACAACAGCGGGAGAAAAAACAGGAUGACUCGUCUAGAAGAGACAUUGUCAGUAACAAGUAAAUAACAUUUUCUGGAAUAUAAAAAAAAAAGCUAUAUGAAUGUCAUCAUUAUAUGUAAAAUAUGAAUGUAAAAUACAUGGGAGGAUAAUAUGCAUUAAUAAAAAUUAUGGUGCUGGCAACAGUA